CGCAAUCAGUUGCGGCGUCCUGUGAGCGCGGGGAUGCUGGGAGGAGGGUGAAAUUUAGCCAUCGGUGUGUGGCAGGGUCAUGAAAAAGCGGCGGCGGCGGGAGAGAGGAGGAGGCGGCGGCGGGGCAGUGAAACUACGGUAGCUGCCCCCUGAGCUGGUGGUGUGGCUUUGUGGGGAGGGCGUAGUUCCUAAUCCCCUUUCCGGGCAGCCGCCGGGGCUCGGGGCUGUGAGCGGCCGUGAGGCUGCCUCCCCGGGCCCCCUGCCUCCGCCAUGUUCCGCAGGGCACGCCUUAGCGUGAAGCCGAAUGUCAGGCCUGGUGUAGGCGCCAGGGGCUCCACAGCUUCCAAUCCCCAGCGUGGACGGGAGUCUCCCAGGCCGCCGGAGCCUGCCACGGACUCUGCUUCCAAGCCCGCGGAGCCCACAGAUGUGCCCACAGUCGAUUUCGGUGGAGCGGAGCCCCAAGAAAAGGCUCCUAGGAGCAGUACUGAAAAGACUGGUGGUGACAAUGAUGUUGAAGAAUCCAGUAGAUCUUCCUCUACUGUUUCACAGAGAAGAAAGCGAAUAUCAAGUACUUCUAGCCUGGUUAAGUCUAGUGUCAGUGUUCCUUCAGAAUCUCAUCCCUUAUCUACAAUUAAUCAAGAGGCUCCACAGCCAACUGCCACUUCAACAAAAGAGAAACAGCCAUGCUCAGACAGAUACCGAAUAUACAAAGCCCAGAAACUGAGGGAAAUGUUAAAAGAAGAAUUGAGAAAAGAGAAGAAACAAUGGAAAAACAAAUAUGCUAUAAAUGAAAGUCAGAGGCCACCAGAUCGUUCAAAAAUGACUAUGAGAGACUUCAUAUAUUAUCUACCAGAUAAUAAUCCAAUGACUUCUUCACUGGAACAAGAAAAGAAAACUGAAAAGCCAUCGACUCCAGUCCAGACAAGAGAGCAAGAAGGUAAGAGUACUCCUAAUGCUGAAGAUAAUGAAAUGGAAGAAGAGACAGAUGAUGGGCCAUUACUGGUUCCUCGAGUAAAAGUGGCAGAAGAUGGUUCCAUUAUUUUGGAUGAAGAAAGUUUAACUGUAGAAGUUUUAAGAACAAAAGGCCCUUGUGUUGUUGAAGAAAAUGACCCCAUAUUUGAGCGCGGUUCUACAACUACAUACUCCAGCUUUAGGAAAAACUAUUACUCUAAACCAUGGUCAAAUAAAGAAACAGAUAUGUUUUUUUUAGCCAUCAGCAUGGUAGGAACUGACUUUUCUAUGAUCGGACAACUUUUUCCUCACAGAGCAAGGAUAGAAAUUAAGAAUAAAUUUAAACGGGAAGAGAAAACAAAUGGAUGGAGAAUAGACAAAGCAUUCCAGGAAAAGCGCCCUUUUGACUUCGAUUUUUUUGCUCAUUUGCUUCAGAAAGUUCUUGCUGAAGAAGAGAAAAGAAAACAAAAAUCUGUUAAAAAUCACAGUUUAAAGGAGAAGAAAUCCACCAAACCACGGAAAAAUGUAAAAGUGAAAAAAGUUGCCUGUGAAGGAGUGAAUAAUGAUCCAGAUGAGUCUAUGAGUUCUAGAAUUUCAGACACGGAAAGAUCUCAGAAGGAUGCUCAGACAGUUGAAGAAGAGUCUCUGACCUUAUCAAGGGAGGAUGCAGAGCAGGUUGCAUUAGAAGUAGACCUAAAUCAAAAGAAAAGAAGGAGGAAGAAGCAAGAUGGAGCUAAUGAACUGGGAGUAAACAAUCUUUUAGAAAAUGCCACUGUUCAGGCGGGUCCUUCUAAAGGAGAAAAACACAAGAAUAAAUGUCAGGCUAUAAGGCCUGAGCUAAAGGAAGGUGAAUGCAGUAAGGAGCAGAUGCUUUCCUGCACACAAAACAUAGAUGGCAUUGUGGGUUUUGCCUCCACUGAAAAAGUUGAGAAAAGAACUGACCCCAUCCUUUCAUUAAGUAAUCAACAAGAUGCCACAUCAGUAGCAACUGAGUCUUCAGAAUCAAGCACUUCAGAUUUGCCUUCAUUCGAAGUUGGAAUUAGAGCAUUGUGUGAGGUGAAUAAUGCUGAGGGUAGUUGUAUAGAAGAAAGAAAUGUUGACCUAAAAAAUAAUUCACUGGAAAUUGAUCAAACAGAAAAUGUUAAACCAAUGUUGAGAGGUCGCUUCCAAAGACCUAAACCCAAUUUGUCAAGGGCUGGGAAGAAAUCAGUUCUUUCACAAGGCAAAACAGAGUCAGAGAGCAAGAAUUCACAUUCAAAAACUUCAGUUGAAAAGAACCACGUGGAAAAAGAUAAAAUGAAUACAUUGGACAUUUUGAGAAUGGAGACUACAGAGAGAGAGAAUCCAGAAGCUGAAACUGUAUCUGUUUUGGGUGAAAAAAAUUGUCUGCAGGAAGGGAGUCAACUAAAGGCUUUAAGACCUGUACAAGUGAGGGGCCGAUUGCAAAAGCCAAAGCCAAAUGCAGGUAAAGCUGCUGAAAGAAAAGAAAUUCUCAUAUCACAGGAAGAAAUUGGGGCCAAUGUAGAGAAGAAUGAAAAUGAAUCCUGUGCUGAUAGAGAUACUCCUCAACACAUGGAAGAUCAAUCGCGUAAAGAUUUUGAAGAGGAAGAUGUCAUAUUACAGCCUGAGAAAAAUGAUUCUUUUCAAAAUGUGCAGCCAGAUGAGCCCAAGGUUCUUAAUGAAUGUCUAAGCGUUCAAGAGAAUAAUAAGGCAAAUAAACUUAACCAAGUCCCAAUUCUAAGGACUCGAUUUCAGAAACCAAAGCCAAAUAUAGGAAGAGGAACUGGAAGGAGAGAAAUUUCCUCAAAGGAAGAGGUACUAGAGAAGAUUCUUGUCUCUGGGGAAAUGGCGGCAGCAUUGAGAGAAACUGUAAGACUAGACACCUCACCAAAGGAGAUGGUACCAGCAGAGAUUAAUACUAAAGAAAUGCAGUCAGAUUUAAAAGAAACUGGAAGAAGAGCCAUUUCUCCCAGGGAGAAGAUUCUAGAUGUGAUUGAUGACACCAUAGAAAUGGAGACAGGUCUGAAAGCAAUGGGAAGAGAGAUUUGUCUAAGGGAGAAGACGCCAGAGGUGAUUGAUGCCACUGAGGAAAUAGACAAAGAUUUGGAAGAAGCUGGAAGAAGAGAAAUAUCCCCACAGAAAAAUGGCCCAGAGGAGGUUAAGCCUCUAGGUGAAGUGGAGACAGAUUUGAAAGCAACUGGAAAUGAGAGUUCCCCAAGGGAGAAGACACCAGAGGUGACUGAUGCCACUGAGGAAAUAGACAAAAAUUUGGAAGAAACUGGAAGAAGAAAAAUAUCCCCAAGGGAAAAUGGCCCAGAGGAGGUCAAGCCUGUAGAUGAAAUGGAGACAGAUUUGAACGCAACUGGAAGAGAGAGUUCUCCAAGGGAGAAGACACCAGAGGUGAUUGAUGCUACUGAGGAAAUAGAUUUGGAAGAAACUGAAAGAGAAGUAUCCCCACAGGAAAAUGGACUAGAGGAGGUCAAGCCUCUAGGUGAAAUGGAGACGGAUUUGAAAGCAACUGGAAGAGACAGUUUCCCAAGGGGGAAGACACCAGAGGUGAUUGAUGCCAUUGAGGAAAUAGAGAUAGAUUUGGAAGAAACUGAAAGAGAAAUAUCCCCACAGGAAAAUGGCCUAGAGGAGGUUAAGCCUCUAGGUGAAAUGCAAACAGAUUUGAAAGCAACCGGAAGGGAGAUUUCCCCAAGGGAGAAGACACCAGAGGUGAUUGAUGCCACUGAGGAAAUAGACAAAGAUCUGGAAGAAACUGGAAGAAGAGAAAUAUCCCCAGAGGAAAAUGGCCCAGAGGAGGUCAAGCCUGUAGAUGAAAUGGAGACAGACUUGAAAACAACUGGAAGAGAGGGUUCCUCAAGGGAGAAGACACGAGAGGUGAUUGAUGCUGCUGAGGUAAUAGAGACAGAUUUGGAAGAAACUGAAAGAGAAAUAUCGCCACAGGAAAAUGGCCCAGAGGAGGUCAAGCCUGUAGGUAAAAUGGAGACAGAUUUGAAAGAAAUUAGAGAAGAAAUUUCCCAAAGGGAAAAGGUGCUAGCAGAGUUCAGUGCUAUAAGGGAAAAGGAGAUUGAUUUGAAAGAAACUGGAAAAAGAGACAUUCCCAUCAUGGAGAAAGUAUCAGGAAAGAUGGCUGUUGUUGAAGAAAUGGAGGCAGAUUUGAAAGAAACUGGAAAAGAAAAUUUUAGAGAGAGAGGAUCUGAAGAGAUCUGUGUUACUGAGGAAAAGGUGGCAGAAUUGAAACAAACUGGAAAAACAGACAUUUCUCCAAGGGAAAACGAGCUAGAGGAGACCAGUACCUCAAGACAAACUGACACACAUUUAAUGCAGAGCGGUAGCAAUGACUUCAGUGCUGUGCCUUCACUAGAUAUUCAGAACAUUAGCAGUGAAGUACUGUCGAUGAUGCAUACACCUGUAGAAGAAAAAAGAAAUUCUGAAAAAGAAGUAUCAAGUCACUUCAGUCAUUUCAAGAUUUCUUCACAGACUCAUGAAUCUGAUAAAACAGAAGUCCAGGGGAUUCAAUCUCCAGAUGUUCCAGAGCAGUUUUCAGAUAUUAAUUUAAGCAAAUCUCUUCCUCAAGAACAGAAGCCACUUGAAAUUAAACCAGCACCUUUUGUGAGGAGCCGAUUCAAAAGACCAAAACCAAACUUAGCAAGAGCAGCUUUGAAGAGAGAGACUACAGAAUCAGAAAAAUAUAUAUAUGAGAAGAAAUCAGAAACCAAGAAAAUGGAGACUAUUGUGAUGCAAGAAAAUAAUGAACAAACUGAUACUCUCCCUUCUCAACAUGAUGAAGCUUCCCUAAUGAUAUCAAGAGAAAAAGACACAUUAGGUCACAGGAAUGAGGAGGCUGUGAUAUUGCCAUGUACACAGACUGAAAGGAACCUUUCACCUUCAAAUUCUUGUGAACCUAAAGAGGAGUCUCAGUCAGCACCAGUCCAGAAAAAUGACUCAGUUGUUUCUGUGGGGACUAAUAAUGUAAACACUUUCCAGCAAGAAAUGAAGGAAAGUGUUAUCCAAACUGCUCGACAAGUAAGGGGCCGACUUCAGAGACCGAGACCAAAUAUAAGAAAGACAGGACAGAGGCAAAUAGUAGACAAAGGUGAAGCCAAAGGCAUAAUUAAGGAAGGAAGAACGAUAUUACCAAAAGAUGAAACUGAAAAGAAAGUCUUAACUGUGUCAAAUUCUCAAAUUGAAACUGAAAUUGAAGUUCCAUCGUCCGCAGUUCCAGAACACAGAAUGUAUGAAAAUCAAAGUCAGGUGGUUCUUGUAGAAAACCUUCAUGUUAACAAAACAAAUGAAACAAUCAGACAUGAAAAUAAACCGUAUGUUCCUAGUUCAGCACAAAUGACAAGAAGGAAAUUCCAAAAGGCUAAGCCAAAUUUGGGAAGAGCACACAGUAAGAAAGAGGAACCAGUUUUAGAAAAAGUCACAACAGAUCAGAGCAAGGAAGGCAAGCCAGAAGAUCAUUUGCUGCAGAAAGGAGCUUCCAACACCCAGCUCCUUCUAAAAGAAAAAGCUGAGCUUCUGACAUCUCUGGAGGUUUCAGCAAGAAAAGAUUGUGUAGGUUCCAAAGAGUCUGCUUUGGCAAAAAUAGAUGCGGAAUUAGAAGAAGUUGGACCAUCAAGAAGGGUUGGAGAGGAAACUGUAGGAGAUAAUUCACCAUCUUCAGUUGUUGAAGAGCAAUAUCUCAAUAAACUAACAAGCUGUCCACAACCGUUAAACGAAACAAGUUACUCUAAAAUUGCCCUGGAUGGGAAAACAACUAUCUCUUCUACAUCUGAGUAUGAGAGAAAUCGUGGUGAAAGGAGAAGUCAUAAAAAGUUCAAACCAAAUGUCACCAGAGGUCGUGGAUCAAAACGAGUUCGGGGUAAGACCUCUAAGAAGGAACCUAGAGCUUCCAAGGCCAUGCUGGUGACUCUUCGGGCUUCCCAGGAAGAAGAUGAUGAUGCUGACGAUUUUGAGUCUGACUAUGAGGAAGAAAGCUAUCAUCUUGCUCCCGAAGAAGUAAACAAAGCUCCAGUAUUUGUACCUGUUGGUCUCAGAUCUCCUGAACCUGUUUCUGCUCAGAUUGAGGAAACAAUGGAAGAGCUUGAAAUAACUGUGAAUGUCCCAGAUGUAGGAUGCAUAGCUGUUGUUGAACAUGAGCUACCAAACACAGAUGUGACUACUGAAGAAAUGAAACAAGAAGAAAAUUUGAGUGUACCGUUUGAAAUGACCACAAGUGAACAUAUCCAAGAUGAACCAGGUACCAAUGAUGGAAGCACCGAAGCUGCAAUAACUUUACUUACAAUGGGAGAUCUAGUAUUGCAGUCAGAGAUCAGUAGUGAACAGGGUGAUGUAGGAGUAUGUAUAAUUCCUCAUGUUCAUUCAAAGGAUAAAAGCCAUAUUCCUUCUAGCCUAGAUAAUGUAAAUCACAAAAUUGUUCAUGAAUGUCAGGAACUUUCUUCACCUGUCAUUACUACAUCUCCUGCAUCAUUUGAAGAAAACAAGAUUGUAUUGGAGGAACAAAGUUCCAGAGAAGAAAUAAGUUUAAUGGAGAAAGUAAAGGAGAAUGCUACACCAACCAGGAAUACAAUUUCUAAAGUGACCAGUAAUUUGAGAAUAAGAAGUAGGCUUGCUAAGCCUAAACCAAAUCUUGAGAAGACUUUAGGGACCAACAGGCUUGAUGAUUAUCAGGAAGUUUCCAGUUUGUGUGUAACCAAAGGGGCAGAAAUGGAAACUCAAAGAGAAACAGAGAAAAAUGCUUCCAAAGCAACAGAAUUGGAAAAUAAAAACCUCGGACCAGUUACAACAGCAGAGAAUAAGGAUCAGAGCAAAUUGGCAUGUGUACAUGGUAUCAAAGGGACCAGUAUUUCUUCAGAAGUAAACCUAACUGAAAGAAACGAAAAUCAAGAAGAGAGCUCUCAGGAGGUUCACAUGUUGUCAGUUGCUCCAGUUGCUUCCUCUGAGACAGGGCCCUGCACACUUGGUUUGGAUAGGGGUCUUGGUGAAAAUUCUGUUGAAGAGCCCCAGAUAAAGGACUCUAAAGGAGACAGUGUGCUUACACUUCCUGUGCCAGAGUAUACACCAACAAGUAUUCCAGAAGUCCAACAAGAGAAUAUAAUCAAUCCUCAAGACCUAACAGUGAAUCUAGUUGCUAAUGUACCUCAAGAUGGAGAAGAUGAACAAGCCUUUAUUUUAACUCUGGUGGAAAUCCCAGCCAAUGCAGUAGAAGAAUUUACUGAUGCCACUGCACAGUUCAUGCCAAACCCUUUACUGCCAGCUCCCAUAUUGGUCAAAUCAGUGAAUACCGAAGAAAGGGGUGACAUGAGUAUUUGUUUACCAGCAACUUCAGUUGGUCAAGAUGCCAUGGGUUUAUCUAUUUCUGGAAGAGAUAAUUCUAAAAAGCCGCCUGAUAAUUUGGAUCUUGUAUCUAGGAAGAGAUUUCAAUGCAGGCUUGAUAAAAAUGACCACAUUCCUCCUGCCAAAAAACGUUCACUCACUUUAAGAGAUGACUGUCAAGAAUAUACCACUGAGGUGCACUCAAAGGAAUUAACAAAUGUUUUUGAGGAAACAGGGGAGUCUCACAAGGGACAAGAUAUUUUUCUUACCUCAGGAAGCACACUGACAACUCCAGAACCUCAAAGACAGCAAGUUGAAGCAGCUUUUCAGAGUAGAGGAUCUAGAUCUCCUGAUGCAUGCAUGGACAAGAAUGUGCCUCAGUUACCUCAGGAUGAAAUGAUUGUGUCUGAUAAGGAAGAAAGAACUGAUGCUGCUCCUAAGUCUCAGCAAAUGGAUAGCAGAACAUCGUCUUCUAAAGCCUCACUAUCCAGACCUGGCAGAAGACCCCUGGGAUUUUUAUCUUUAAUAUGCUCAAAGAAUAGUUUGGAGUCUGAUGAACCUAUGCAAGUCCAUAGUAAGAAACGCCUAAAACCUCUUAUACCUGGAUUAAGAAAGAAAUUGAAAAGAUCUAAUCCAUUCAAUGAAAGCCAGGAAAAAAAUCGAGAGUCCUCUGAUCUGCUUCCAUCUCCAAGUGUUAUUACUACUCAAUCUGAGAAUAUUAGCAGCUCAGCAACUCAGAGACCCUUCUGACUUGUGGAAGCAAAAGGAAGCAGUGCUGACACCCACAAGAAUUUAAGGAACUGUAAAACUAGAAUUUGUUCACAUGUUUCAUUUCUAUGUCUCCUGAAGCUGUCCAAUGGCAAGUAUUGGGAUGGAAAACUCUGUAAACCUGUAUCAAAGACUUUGUAAAAAUAUUGGGGUGACUUAAGAUCUUGACAAAGAGAAGGCUGGUGAGCAUCUGUUGAACAGCAUGAGCCUUUGGAAGGGGUACUUUUGUAAAGAACAUCUUUAAACUUUUUAAAAACAUUUUGUAUUAUUUGUUAGAAUUAUUUUCUGAGAUCAAGAUAUCAGUCUAGCUUAUCAUUGCCAAAGUCGUGGGUUUUGUUUUUUUUGUGUGUUUGUUUUGAGACAGAGUCUCACUCACUCUGUCACCCAGGCUGUAGUGCAGUGGCGUGAUCUUGGUUCACUGCAACCUCCAUCCCCUGGGUUCAAGUGAUUCUCCUGUCUCAGCUUCUCGAUUAGCUGAGCUUACAGAUGCAUGCCACAACACCCAGCUAAUUUUUGUAUCUUUAGUAGAGGCGGGAUUUCGCCAUGUGGGCCAUGCUGUUCUCAAAUGCCUGGCCUCAAGCCUUGGCCUCCCAAAGUGUUGGAAUUACAGGCAUGAGCCACUGUGCCUGGCCUGUAGUGUUCUUAUUAUAUUCAGGGAAAAAGGCCCUUUGUGAUAAAGAUUGCAAUUUUUUUUUUCUCUGUAUGUCAUUUGUCUUUUGAUUUUAUUUAUGGUGGUUUUUGUCAAGCAGACAUUUUUUAUUUCUGUUUAAUUUGUCAAUCUUUUAUAGCUUUCUGCUUUCAGAUAGUUUAAAAAGGUACUCUUCCCAGCUGGGUGCGGUGGCUCACGCCUGUAAUCCCAGCACUUUGGGAGGCCAAGGCGGGCAGAUCACCUGAGGUGAGGAGUUUGAGACCAGCCUGGCCAACAUGGCAAAACCCCAUCUCUACCAAAAUACAAAAUUUAAUCAGGCACGGUGGUGUGUGCCUGUAGUCCCAGCUACUUGGGAGGCUGAGAUAAGAGAAUUGCUUGAACCCGGGAGGUGGAGGUUGCAGUGGGCUGAGAUCAUGCCAUUGCAUUCCAGCCUGGCUUUGUCUUAAAAUAAAUAAAUAAAUAAAAAGGUACCCUUCCCCACCUACCUCCGUCCAGAAUUAUAAAAGUGUUUUUCCAUGGCAUUUUUAUAGUAGAGUUUUUUAAAAAAUACUUUUACAUUUAAAUCUUUUGAUCCAUCUAGAAUUUGUUUUGGUAAGGUAUUGGUCUGACUUUUUUCCCCCUGAGAUGGUUAUAUAGUUGUCCAACAUCAUUUAUUUAAUAAUACAAUAACUGUUUUUGAUAUGGCACUUUUAUCAGAUGCUAAAUUUCUAUAUAUAUUGGGGUUAUUUCUAGUCUUCUGUUUCAUUGAUAUAUCUGUCAUUCGUGUGCCAAUACCAUGCUGUCUUAAUUUGUUUAUAGAUUUGUAAGUAUGCUAAUUUCUGAUAAGGUAUCUUUGAUAUGUUUUCUUUAGGUGCUGUUUUGUCAUGGGUCUGUCUAUUAUGCAAAUAAUUAAAGUAUUUUUACUUUAUUUAGUGACAGAUUUAACCAUAUUAUAUUUUUCUUUAUUAAAAUUUUUCAUGGAAAUUAGGAUGAAGUAAUGGAUUAUGGGUACACUGUAAUUUACCUAAUUAUAUCUAGUGUGGUAUAUUUAGUUGCUUCCUAUUUUAUUAUUAUAACUAAUGCUACAAAGGUUAUCUUAGUCAUAAAACUCCUACUAUGUUUAGGAUUAUUUACUUAAUGUAACAGCAUAGAAGUGAAAUUUUUGGGUCAGUGAUUGUGAACAUAUUUAAAGCUCAAUAUUUAUUGCCACGUUGCUUUUCAAACAGAUCAUAUUGGUUUAGACUGCUAUAUAUACACACACAUAUAUAUAUAAAUGUUGUAUUACAGUUUUAUUUUUACUUUAUUUUUAUUACCUUUUUAGGUUUCUUGUGAUCAGCCCUUACUGAAAGAAGGAUAUAAAAGUGCCCAAAAGCGGGCCCCUCAAGGGGAGGCAACCACAGUCUCUGAAUAUUUCUUCAAUGAUAUCUUCAUUGAAGUGGAUGAAACAGAAUAAAACAAUCUUUUCUCUUUUUCUUUUUUAAAUUAGGUCUAGGAUUUCCAGAGUCAAUUACAUCAACAAAACAGUAUUUAGAGCAAAAUAUCACUGUCUUAUUUUUCUUUAGGUUGAUUUUGAAUACUUAAUGAGCUUGAUUUGAAGCUUUUAUAAUCAGUGGAAAACAUUUCUGAGGUUCCUUUCAUUCUGACUGAUUCAGCAUUUUGCAAAUAGCAAGCAAUUAAGACUGCUUUCUCAGACAGAAAUAACAACUCUUGUUUACAUUUUGACUCUUCCUGUGCUAAGCACACAUGGACAUUUGGGAAUGUUGUGGAUAUAUGUCUCUGUAUGAAUUGCAGUGCAGACAGAUUUGGGGGUUAAUUGUAUCAUAUUUAACAUUUAGCAACUUCUUUUGUGAAGAUUUUUUAUUUUUAGGGGGAGAUGAUGAAGGAUGAAGGCUUUUUCAUUUGCUUCUAAGUACAGUCAUGUAUCACAUAAUGAAGUUUAAGUCAAUGAUGGACCACAUAUAUUACAGUGGUCCCAUGCAAUUAAAAUGGAGAUAAAUUCCUAUCAACUAGUGACAUUAUAGCCAUCAUAACACAGUGCAUUGCUUUUUUAUGUUUAGAUAUGUUUAGAUACACAAAUACUUACUAUUGUGUUACAACUGCCUACAGUAUUCAGCAUAGUAACACAUUGUAGAGGUUUGUAGCCGAGGAGCAAUAGGCUAUACCACAUAGCCUCAGUCUGUACGGUGUGUAGCAGCCUGUACCAUCUCAGUGUUUGUAAGUACACUCUGCGUUGUUUCACACAAGAUCACCUAACAAGGCAAUUCUUAGAACAUGUAGUUAAGGGACACGUGACUAUAUGUGAAAACAAAUUGUCAAACUUCACUUUAGUAUGGCAAAUGUUAAAGAACUUUUCUAUUAUCAGCUGUUUGUCUGACUGAAAAAUACAUAUUUUUCUAAUUCAUGGUGAUGUAACAUUAGUCCUAAUUGAAAAACUAGUAUUUAAACAUAAUUAUUUAUAAAGAUGACACAUCAAAGGGCUUAUUUAUUUUUAAAUUUUUUAUUUAAAAGGAUAUUCAGUUUUAGCUAUUUUUACCCCUCAGAUUGUAGAUAAAGAAGGCAUUAAAUUUAUGUUUGUCUCCUUUUUCUGUUUAAUUUUAAAGAUAUUUAAAAUGAUAUAACUAAAAAUGUUUAGCUGGUGUAUAUGUUUUGAAUACCUUUUUCCCCUCAGUUUAGUAUAUUGACUUUGUACUGUAAAUUUUUCUGCUUUUCUUGGAUAAUCUCAGGAUUUUCAUGAGGAUAGGGGGAACUCAACUUUAUUUAUGAGACAAAAUUUCCAUACAAAGCUCAAUCUCCUUUAUACACCCACAGACAUAAUAUUAGUUUUUAAAAAGCCAAUUUCUUCAUAGUUUUUUCCCAUUAAAUUCUCAAGGAACACUUGGAUCUUUAAGCACGGAACAUAAUCAUGAUGUUAAAAACAGAGAAAAUAAGGCUUUAUAAAGUUAAUGAUUAUCAUCAGUAUGAAUUUAAGGUUUGUUUUAAUUUCAAGAUUUGAUUUUUUAUACGUGUAAUUCUAUUAUCUACCCAAGCAGAUCUGUAGUGGUUCCAAUUAGACUUCUCAAACAGCAAAUUUAUCCUGAUUUUAUUUGAAAAGCCUCUUGGAUUGAUAGUAUAGUAGCUCAGGCAUUGGAAACUUUCUGCAAACUGUUUUGGGUUUGCAGGCCAGAUGGUCUCUGUGGCAGCUACUCAGCUCUGCAAUUUCAGUGUGAAAGAAGCCAUAGACAGUACUUGAAUGAAGGACUGUGGCUGGAUUGGCCUUUUAGUUUGACCCCCUACAUUAGGCCCCAAAUUUUCUUACCCUGAGGUGCUGAUAUCUGUAUGGAUGAGUUAUUUGUCACUAAAGUUAUGAGUUGUGCCUAAAAGUUAAAACUGUUGACUGUAUUAUGUAAUGAUCAGUAUUUCAGUUGGGAAGAUAUUUUAGAGUCUAGAUAAUUAUGUUUGUAUAUUGAAAAAAUGGUGGCCAGUUUUUAAGUUCCUUAAUAGAAGAGAAUUAUGUCUCAGCACAUAUAACAGUAAUGCUAAUUUAUUGAAACUACUGCUGUUAGAGCACUUCUUAUUCAUUGUCUUUUAGUGAAAUUUAUGGCGUAACACUUUGUCAGAGAGGAGGCUAUAUAAUUCGGAGCGGAAAUUGUCUAUAAGUAGGCAUUUAUUUCAUGAUUGAUAUGUCACAGAAAUCAUGGUAGUAAAUCACAUUGCUAUUUGAAUACCCUGUUUUUGUAAGUUUUUAAAACUCAUAUUCUGAAAAGAUUUCAUUCUCUUAGUGUUAGCUUGGGAGUUAGAUUGCCAUGAUUAAACUAUUAUUUAUCCUUGUGUAAUAUUAGUUUUUAACUUUAACAUCUGUUUCUUUUUAAUCUAUAAUGAGCUAGUUUUAUGGAAAAUGGAAUUUCUUACUAUAUAAAGAAUACAGAGACUCAUUGUAUUAGAGAAUCAAGUCAGCCAGCUAAAGUAUCCUACUGUUAAAUCCUUAAACCUAAUUUUGGAAAAGAGAAAGUUAAUCAAUGUAUUUACCUUACAUGUUGGAAAGAACUAUGUUAGGUCUGAUUCAUGUGAAGAAGAUGUUGCAAAGGAUUUAUUUCACAAAUUUUAAAGGAGAUAUGAGUAAAAGUUUUUAUCUUUUCUUGACUUUUUCUCCUGAACACUUAUGUCUUAGCAAGUGGUCAACAUGAGGAUUUGAACGCCUAAUUGUUGGUAAAUGGUUGAGGCAUGACAAAAAUAUUAAUAUCCACUGUUUACCAUCAUGUUAUUUGAAACAAAAGUGACCAUGUAUACUAUCUUGCUUGAAGAAGUCUUUGACAGAAAAAGCAAUAUCAUGUCAUUUAUAAAUUUUCUUGUUCUAAAGAAAGCAGUUAUAUAUAUAUAUAAAUUAUGUAAAUAAAAGUUAUUUUAUAUCA